UUUUUUUUUUUUGAGACGGAGUCUCACUCUGUCACCCAGGCUGGAGUGCAGUGGUGCGAUCUCGGCUCACUGCACGCUCCGCCUACCGGGUUCACGCCAUUCUCCUGCCUCAGCCUCCUGAGUAGCUGGGACUACAGGCACCCACCAGCAUGCCUGGGUAAUUUUUUGUAUUUUUUUUAGUAGAGACGGGAUUUCACUGUGUUAGCCAGAAUGAUCUCGAUCUUCUGACCUCGUGAUCCGCCCACCUCAGCCUCCCAAAGUGCUGGGAUUACAGGCGUGAGCCACCGCGCCCGGCCUGUUUUUACCUUUUGGUUAUUGUGAACAAUGCUGCUAUGAACAUUCGUAUAUGGGUAUCUGUUCAGGUCUCUGCUUCCAGUUUCUUUUGGGUCUGUACUUAGAAGUGAAAUUGCCGAAUCGUAUGGUAGUUUUGUGUUUAACUAUUUAAGGAACUGCUGUAAAUCCUUUGAAGCCAUUAACAGUUUUGAAGAAAUUUAGCAAAUUUAUUUAUUUAGCAAGUGUUUAUUAAGUGCCCACCACGUCCUGUGCACAUCAUGUUCUAGGCACUUUGCCAAAACAUUUCUCCUUGUCUUCUGCGCAGAAAGAUGAUGCCAACUGAGUGUGUUCUCCACUGAGUGGCACAGAGGCUUUUAACACAUGGGGCAGCAGAAUGACACAGGGAAGGGAUGACUGUCUUCGGAGACAUUCACUCACUGCGGUUGCUGUUGACAUGUUAUUAAGGAAAAGCGGGAUGCCUAUGUGAGCCGCCUGAAUGCCAUCUAUCAAAACAAUCUCACCAAGUCCCAUAUAGAAAUCAUCCGUGGCCAUGCAGCCUUCACGAGUGAUCCCAAGCCCACAAUAGAGGUCAGUGGGAAAAAGUACACCGCCCCACACAUCCUGAUCGCCACAGGUGGUAUGCCCUCCACCCCUCAUGAGAGCCAGAUCCCCGGUGCCAGCUUAGGAAUAACCAGCGAUGGAUUUUUUCAGCUGGAAGAAUUGCCCGGCCGCAGCGUCAUUGUUGGUGCAGGUUACAUUGCUGUGGAGAUGGCAGGGAUCCUGUCAGCCCUGGGUUCUAAGACAUCACUGAUGAUACGGCAUGAUAAGGUACUUAGAAGUUUUGAUUCAAUGAUCAGCACCAACUGCACGGAGGAGCUGGAGAACGCUGGCGUGGAGGUGCUGAAGUUCUCCCAGGUCAAGGAGGUUAAAAAGACUUUGUCGGGCUUGGAAGUCAGCAUGGUUACUGCAGUUCCCGGUAGGCUACCAGUCAUGACCAUGAUUCCAGAUGUUGACUGCCUGCUCUGGGCCAUUGGGCGGGUCCCGAAUACCAAGGACCUGAGUUUAAACAAACUGGGGAUUCAAACCGAUGACAAGGGUCAUAUCAUCGUAGACGAAUUCCAGAAUACCAACGUCAAAGGCAUCUAUGCAGUUGGGGAUGUAUGUGGAAAAGCUCUUCUUACUCCAGUUGCAAUAGCUGCUGGCCGAAAACUUGCCCAUCGACUUUUUGAAUAUAAGGAAGAUUCCAAAUUAGAUUAUAACAACAUCCCAACUGUGGUCUUCAGCCACCCCCCUAUUGGGACAGUGGGACUCACGGAAGAUGAAGCCAUUCAUAAAUAUGGAAUAGAAAAUGUGAAGACCUAUUCAACGAGCUUUACCCCGAUGUAUCACGCAGUUACCAAAAGGAAAACAAAAUGUGUGAUGAAAAUGGUCUGUGCUAACAAGGAAGAAAAGGUGGUUGGGAUCCAUAUGCAGGGACUUGGGUGUGAUGAAAUGCUGCAGGGUUUUGCUGUUGCAGUGAAGAUGGGAGCAACGAAGGCAGACUUUGACAACACAGUCGCCAUUCACCCUACCUCUUCAGAAGAGCUGGUCACACUUCGUUGAGAACCAGGAGACACGUGUGGCGGGCAGUGGGACCCAUAGAUCUUCUGAAAUGAAACAAAUAAUCACAUUGACUUACUGUUUGAGUUUUAUGUAUUUCUUUAUUUUAAUCAGGAUCUUCUGAUAGUGGAAAUUUUUAGUACAUAAUAGAACUUAUUUAUGGAGUUAGAAAUUUGUAGUGUUAUCCAGGAUUGAUUUUCAUUUGAUCACAUCUCACAGUAAUUAAUAUUUUCAAGUUUUUUUUUUAUUAACAGCUCUGUGCUAGUUUUUUUUUUCUGUUUUAGCCUCAUCCCAAAUAUAAAGCUUUGUGAAGUACAAUUAACUUAAUGUACUUGAAUGAAUAGAACUUGCUACUUUUUUUUUUUUUUUUUUUGAGACAGAGUUUUGCUCUCAUUGCCCAGGCUGGAGUGCGGUGGUGCUAUUUCAGCUCACCACAACCUCUGCCUCCUGGGUUCAAGUGAUUCUCCUGCCUUAGCCUCCCGAAUAGCUGGAAUUACAGGCACGCACCACCAUGCCUGACUAAUUUUGUAUUUUUAGUAGACAUGGGGUUUCUCCAUGUUGGUCAGGCUGGUCUCAAACUCCCACCUUCAGGUGAUCCGCCCACCUCGGCCUCCUGAGGUGCUGAGAUUACAGGCGUGAGCCACUGUGCCAGCUUGCUAAUUUUCACAGAAGUUGAUGGCAAUUCUUCACAUGUAAACAGUGCCAGUGCACAGAACCUUUAUAUAUUUUUUGAAGCCAGUACUGUGCUCUGCAUAUAACAAAGCUGCUUCAAGGAUGAGACCUUUUUCUAAAAGCAUGUAAUGUGAGAAGCCGGCCUGCCUUAUUUUCUUUUUUCUUUUUUAAUGAUUAAAAAUAGUUUGUGGCAAGGCACGGUGGCUCAGGCCUGUAAUUCUAGCACUUUGGGAGGCCGAGGCAGGAGGAUUACUUGAGCCUACAAGUUUGAGGCCAGCAUGCACAGCAUAGCAAGACUGCAUCUCUACAGAGAGUAAAAAAAAUUACCCGAGUGUGGUGAUGUGCAUCUGUAAUCUCAGCUACUUGGGAGGCUGAGGUGAGAGGAUCACUUGAGCUUGGGUGAGGUGAGGCUGCAGUGAGUCCUGAUCAUGCUGCUGCACUCAAUCUUGGACAACAGAGCAAGACCCUGUCUCAAAAAAAAAAAAAAAAAAUAUAUAUAUAUAUAUAUAUUAUUUUUAUGAGGUGAAGUGCAUCAAACUUGGGAAAGAUUUGAGGAGGCUGGGAACCUCCUGGAAAACCACUCCUUGAAGAAAGAUAUGAGAGACAUUUAGAAGUGAUUCCUGCUUUCAGAAGGAGGUGGAUUCAAAUACAUCAAAAGUCCCUUCCUCUGCUAAGUGUUUAUAGUUCAAUGAAUAAUUUCAAUAUUUGUAUGUGUUCUUGUCAUUUUAUUUUUUUCUGAAAAACUUCCAAAAAUUUGAAAAUAAAAUUACAGCCUUUUCUUCUUA